GCGCCGCCCCGCGCCGGCUCCGCAGCUCGCGCCCGCCCGCCUGCCGGCCCGCCCGGCGCCGGGCCAUGGCGCUGCUGCGGGAUGUGUCGCUGCAGGACCCGCGGGACCGCUUCGAGCUGCUGCAGCGCGUGGGGGCCGGGACCUAUGGCGACGUCUACAAGGCCCGCGACACGGUCACGUCCGAACUGGCCGCCGUGAAGAUAGUCAAGCUAGACCCAGGGGACGACAUCAGCUCCCUCCAGCAGGAAAUCACCAUCCUGCGUGAGUGCCGCCACCCCAAUGUGGUGGCCUACAUUGGCAGCUACCUCAGGAAUGACCGCUUGUGGAUCUGCAUGGAGUUCUGCGGAGGGGGCUCCCUGCAGGAGAUUUACCAUGCCACUGGGCCCCUGGAGGAGCGGCAGAUUGCCUACGUCUGCCGAGAGGCACUGAAGGGGCUCCACCACCUGCAUUCUCAGGGGAAGAUCCACAGAGACAUCAAGGGAGCCAACCUUCUCCUCACUCUCCAGGGAGAUGUCAAACUGGCUGACUUUGGGGUGUCAGGCGAGCUGACAGCGUCUGUGGCCAAGAGGAGGUCUUUCAUUGGGACUCCCUACUGGAUGGCUCCCGAGGUGGCUGCUGUGGAGCGCAAAGGUGGCUACAAUGAGCUAUGUGACGUCUGGGCCCUGGGCAUCACUGCCAUUGAGCUGGGCGAGCUGCAGCCCCCUCUGUUCCACCUGCACCCCAUGAGGGCCCUGAUGCUCAUGUCGAAGAGCAGCUUCCAGCCGCCCAAACUGAGAGAUAAGACUCGCUGGACCCAGAAUUUCCACCACUUUCUCAAACUGGCCCUGACCAAGAAUCCUAAGAAGAGGCCGACAGCAGAGAAGCUCCUGCAGCACCCGUUCACGACUCAGCAGCUCCCUCGGGCCCUCCUCACACAGCUGCUGGACAAAGCCAGUGACCCUCAUCUGGGGACCCCCUCCCCUGAGGACUGUGAGCUGGAGACCUAUGACAUGUUUCCAGACACCAUUCACUCCCGGGGGCAGCACGGCCCAGCCGAGAGGACCCCCUCGGAGAUCCAGUUUCACCAGGUGAAAUUUGGCGCCCCACGCAGGAAGGAAACUGACCCACUGAAUGAGCCGUGGGAGGAAGAGUGGACACUACUGGGAAAGGAAGAGUUGAGUGGGAGCCUGCUGCAGUCGGUCCAGGAGGCCCUGGAGGAAAGGAGUCUGACUAUUCGGUCAGCCUCAGAAUUCCAGGAGCUGGACUCCCCAGACGAUACCAUGGGAACCAUCAAGCGGGCCCCGUUCCUAGGGCCACUCCCCACUGACCCUCCAGCAGAGGAGCCUCUGUCCAGUCCCCCAGGAACCCUGCCCCCACCUCCUUCAGGCCCCAACAGCUCCCCACUGCUGCCCACGGCCUGGGCCACCAUGAAGCAGCGGGAGGAUCCUGAGAGGUCAUCCUGCCACGGGCUCCCCCCAACUCCCAAGGUGCAUAUGGGCGCCUGCUUCUCCAAGGUCUUCAAUGGCUGCCCCCUGCGGAUCCACGCUGCUGUCACCUGGAUUCACCCUGUUACUCGGGACCAGUUCCUGGUGGUAGGGGCCGAGGAAGGCAUCUACACACUCAACCUGCAUGAACUGCAUGAGGAUACGCUGGAGAAGCUGAUUUCACAUCGCUGCUCCUGGCUCUACUGCGUGAACAACGUGCUGCUGUCACUCUCAGGGAAAUCCACGCACAUCUGGGCCCAUGACCUCCCAGGCCUGUUUGAGCAGCGGAGGCUACAGCAACAGGUUCCCCUCUCCAUCCCCACCAACCGCCUCACCCAGCGCAUCAUCCCCAGGCGCUUUGCUCUGUCCACCAAGAUUCCUGACACCAAAGGCUGCUUGCAGUGUCGUGUGGUGCGGAACCCCUACACGGGUGCCACCUUCCUGCUGGCCGCCCUGCCCACCAGCCUGCUCCUGCUGCAGUGGUAUGAGCCGCUGCAGAAGUUUCUGCUGCUGAAGAACUUCUCCAGCCCUCUGCCCAGCCCAGCUGGGAUGCUGGAGCCGCUGGUGCUGGAUGGGAAGGAGCUGCCGCAGGUGUGUGUUGGGGCCGAGGGGCCUGAGGGGCCCGGCUGCCGCGUCCUGUUCCAUGUCCUGCCCCUGGAGGCUGGCCUGACGCCCGACAUCCUCAUCCCACCUGAGGGGAUCCCAGGCUCGGCCCAGCAGGUGAUCCAGGUGGACAGGGACACAAUCCUAGUCAGCUUUGAACGCUGUGUGAGGAUUGUCAACAUGCAGGGCGAGCCCACGGCCACACUGGCACCUGAGCUGACCUUUGAUUUCCCCAUCGAGACUGUGGUGUGCCUGCAGGACAGUGUGCUGGCCUUCUGGAGCCAUGGGAUGCAAGGCCGAAGCCUGGAUACCAAUGAGGUGACCCAGGAGAUCACAGAUGAAACAAGGAUCUUCCGAGUGCUUGGGGCCCACAGAGACAUCAUCCUGGAGAGCAUUCCCACUGACAACCCAGAGGCGCACAGCAACCUCUACAUCCUCACGGGCCACCAGAGCACCUACUAAGAGCAGCGGGCCUGUCCAGGGGCUCCCCGCCCCACCCCACGCCUUAGCUGCAGGCCCUUUUGGGCAAAGGGGCCCAUCCUAGACCAGAGGAGCCCAGGCCCUGGCCCUGCUGGGGCUGAAGGUCAGAAGUAAUCCUGAGAAAUGUUUCAGGCCUGGGGAGGGAGGGGAGCCCCCGACGCCUCUGCAAUAACUGGACCAGGGGGAGCUGCUGUCACUCCCCCAUCCCCGAGGCAGCCCAGUCCCUAGUGCCCAAGGCAGGGACCCUGGGCCUGGGCCAUCCAUUCCAUUUUGUUCCACAUUUCCUUUCUACUCUUUCUGCCAAGAGCCUGCCCCUGCAUUUGUCCUGGGAAACACGGUAUUUAAGAGAGAACUAUAUUGGUAUUAAAGCUGGUUUGUUUUAGUCCUCUGGUCCCUCUGGGUAGGGGGAGUGAACCCACCUCAUCUCCCGCCUCCUUCCCUCCAACACACGUUUCUGUGGGCACCACAGAAGGGCAGGGCCCCCAGGGUUUUGGAGAAGCCAGGUAGAGGUGACAGGAGGCCAUGGCCCCCAGCAGCCUUCUAGGGGCACUGUGCCUUCCCCUGCAUCCUUGCUCAGAACUGACCCUCAGCUUUGCAGUUUGAGGGCUCUGCUGUAGUUUAGCACCCCAAGGACUCAUGCAGAUGGGGGGACCUCAACAAAGGGACUCUCAUCCAGGGCACCCUUGCCCCACGUAGGAUCUCACUGGGUGACCCCUGGAAGGGCCCAGGAGGAGCCCCCAGAGGGCUGUUCCCUCCAUUCCCAUGGAGGCUGCUGCCCAUGGAGGUAGCCUGUGUGACCUGUAUCCCCUGCCUCCACCUACUGCCUAGGUGUUAGACCAGGAACAUCAGAUGACAGCACGAUCAUCAGAUUGGAUGGGAAGGCUAGCCUGUGUCCGUCUACCAGACUCCCAAGGGCUGCCUCAGUGCCAGGCCCUGGGGUCACUACCAGAAACAGACCAGCCCCCAGGGAGGGCGUCCUCCUUGCUGGAGCCUGCAUCUUGAGGGCAUGGCCAUUCUCCUGUAGCUUGUGCUUACGCUGUCAUUCUCCAAGGGUCUGUCUGCUCAGCUCUGAAUGCCAGGGCCCCCAGGGCUGGGCAUCCUCUUUUGCCCCAGGCACUGAUCAGCCGCUCUUGACUGGAGCCUUUGGGCAGCUGCAGCCCAGGAGGCAGGAUGGGAACUGCCUUGAGGGCCCACAGCUGGGGGGCUGGGAAGGUGGGGGCAGGGUGGGGGGAACAGCUGGAGCAAAGGCCCCAUGGUCACCCCUACAUUCAAGGCAGGUGUUGGAGGAAGACCUUUGCACCUGGUGGGUGGCAAUAAAGACUUGCGGAGUGACGUGGUAGGUGGAUGGCAGCCAUGCGAGUAGGCUCAGUGGUUCCCAGGGUGUCACACUGUCCCCUCAGCCACCCUCCAGCAGAGUUUCAACUGUUCUGACUCUGUCCAGUGACUGGGAGGGUUUCUUGGCUGGAAUGGGGAGCCAGCCCAGGGGAGGGAACACAUCUCUUCACACCAGGCAUUCACACCCAUGUUCCCGUGAGCCCCAAGGAGGGUGAGGGGCACCUUCCAAAUUGGGGUCGGUGGUAACAGGGAUACAAAGUGAAUUCCUAACUUCCAAUUUUCCAGAUUUCUCGGAGGAAUGUUGGGACCAGGGUGGGGUAAGUGGGGACAGGGAGGUGAGCUCCUGCUCAGCAAAGGCCCUGACCAAAGGCGCCCUGGGGAGGACUGGCUUUCCGUUCACCAACCGGCCAGCAGCAGACAGUGCCUCCUUGUGGCGGAUCUUCCCGGACCUCAGAUUCAGUCUGGAAACGGGGUUUGGACUGCAGAGUGUAAACUGCCAAAGUGGGGGCCUCCCAUAAAACGCUUGCUGCCAGCAAAGGCAGGCCAAGAGCAAAGAAAGGCCGAGAAACCAGGGAAUAUGCACUGAGAGACUAACACUUUAAAUUUUAUUUAUGUAUUUUUAAAUGCGUAACCUUUGCCCAUGGUACAUAUUUUUUUAAAUACAGCAGAGAUAUAAUGAAGUCUCCCUCUUACCCCGUCCCCAGCCACCCUGGUCUCAGUUACUUAUGAACCCUUCUAGAAGUAUUUUGCGUAUUUAAGCAAUUUGGUAUAUUUUAUUCUUGGCGAUUUUUUAUAUACGUAUUAACAUAUUCCACAUACUGUACUGACCUUGCCCUUUAAAAAUAUAUCCUGGGGGGCCAGGUGUGGUGGCUCACACCUGUAAUCCAAGCACUUUGGGAGGCCGAGGCGGGCGAAUCACGAGGUCAGGGGUUCGAGACCAGCCUGGCCAACAUGGUGAAACCCCGUCUCUACUAAAAAUACAAAAAAUUAGCUGGGCAUGGUGGCGAGUGCCUGUAAUCCCAGCUACUCGGGAGGCUGAGGCAGGAGAAUCGCUUGAACCUGGGAGGCGGAGGUUGCAGUGAGCCUAGAACAUGCCACUGCACUCCAGCCUGGGCGACAGUGCAAGACUCCGUCUCAAAAAAAAAAAAAAGAGAAAAAAAUAUAUAUAUAUCCUGGAGAAUAUGAAUGUAUUAAAUUAUCACAUGCACCCUGAAAAGAUAUGUAUAUAUCCUGGAGAGUUUUGCGUUAAAGAUCUCCCUUUAAAAAAAAAUUUUUUUUUUUUUACAGCUAGUGGUAUUCCAUUGUGUAUGUUUCCCAUAACAAAUGUUAAUGACCUGCAGUGAGAUCCCUAUUGGUGGAAAUUUGAGUUGUUUUUACUACUUUUAUAUUACAAACAAUGCUGCAAUAAAUAUUAUUAGGCUAGUGCCCCUCUGUACAUAUUCAAGCACUUCUAGAAGAUAAGUUCCUGGAAGCAGCAUUAAUGAGUUAGCGGUGGCUACAUAUGCCGUGGUGAUAGCUGCUGUCCAGUUGCCCCUCCAUGGGCAGAAACCUGUGGGAGGGUCAGACCAGACUCUUUAAGUCAUUCUUGAGGACAAGUAGAAGGGACGUGGGCCCCCCCAGGAUGUUCAGGUAACUGGCCCAUACCCGGAGUCAUCCUGGUGAAAGUCAAGGGGAGCACCAUGAUGUGUGCUUCGGGACGGCGGAGGAUCUGCCGUGUUCCCUGUGGCAUGUCCAGCACCUGCUCACUACCAGUGCUCAGGAGACCCUCACGAGUAAGGGAAUGGACAAGAUGUGGUGAAGAGGAGUCCCUGCAAUCUGCCCUUGGACUGGGUGAGCCACCCCAGCUCGCUGAGCUUUACUUUCCUUAGGUUUACCAUAUCCAAAGCCAACUGCAGGGCUGUCAGGAGGAUCAGAAAUACUGUAACAGACAUAAUGCAAUAACAUAGAUGACUCUUAGAGGUAAAUUAAAACAGCACUUUAUGCACAGUACGAUAGCAUAUUAUAAAGCUCAAAAACAAAAUGAAACCAUCUAUUGUUUAGCAAUACAUGCCCAAGAUACAACCCUAUUAAAAAAUCAUGGGAAGGAAAAGCACAAAAUCUGAGAUGGUCGUCCCUGAGAGGAGUGUGGGAUGGGAUAAGGAAGGAGCCCAGGAAUUUUUAAAGGUAUUGGUAAUAUCUUAGCUCUCAGGUUUGGUGGUAGGUUCAUGGGUAUUUAAGUUAUAACUCAGUUCCUAACUCACAUAAGGUGCCACACAUCCUUUUGUAUGUAUCAAAUAUUAUGUCAUAAAAUUUUAGUUUGGGCAUGGUGGUUCAUGUCUGUAAUCCCAGCACUUUGGGAAACUGAGGCAGGCAGAUCACUUGAACCCAGGAGUUCUAGACCAGCCUGGGCAACAUGACAAAACCCUGUCUCUACAAAAGAUACACAAAUUAGCUGGACAUGGUGGCACUCGCCUGCAGUCCCAGCUACUCUGGAGGCUAAGGUGGGAGGAUUGCUUGAGCCUAGGAGUUCAAGGCUGCAGUGAGCUAUGAACUUGCCACUGCACUCCAGCCUGGGUGACAGAGUGAGAACCUGUCUCAAAAAGAAAAAAAAAAAAAGGAAAAAAAUUUUUAAAAAAUAUUUAAAAGUAAUCACCGAAAAAAUAGAACUCGCUUGAAAGACAAGACCAAAAACGAAGAGGACGUUUCCCUAGAUGGUGAAAACAAGUGGGGCGGAAUCACUGCAGCGUCCUGCACAGAACUCUGGAAUUGCCACUUUGCAGUUGCUGCCUUCUAGUGUGUAUUGUUGAAAGACAGUUUUAUUGAGGCAUAAUUGGCAUACAAUAAGCUGCAUAUAAAAAUGUGUACGUGAUGACUUUUGACAUACGUGUACACCCGUGAAGCUAUUUCCACAAUCAAGAUAAUCACCAUCCCCUUCACUCUGGAAAGUUUCCCAUGCCCUUGGUAAGCCCACCCUCCUGCUUCUUGCCUCCCAUCCCCAAGUAACAACUGUGCUGCUUUCUGUCACUACAGGUUAAUCUGCACUUUCUAGAAUGUAUGUAAAUAGAAUCACACAGUAUGUACUUGUGUUUUGUCUGGCUUCUUGCUUAGCUGAGCAUAAGGAUUUGCGAGUCAUCCCUGUUGCAUGCAUUAAUAUUUUAUUCCUUUUUAUUGCCAAGUAGUAUUCCAUUGUUUGGAUGCACCAGUUUGGUUAGCUGUUCACCUGUUGAUGGACAUUUGGACCAUGUUCCGUUGUGAACUAUUACAAAUAAAGCUGCUAUAAACAUUCA